AGGCAGAUCUCGCUUCCGCCGGUGGGACGGAACUGGUGCCCUCCGUGGACAAUUGUGUUGAAGCAGAAAUUGUUCCGGAUCUCGGGUCGGACACGGAAGUCUUCCUGCAGUGUUUCUGGAUGCGGGGACAGGGAUGCGCAGGAAUUCCAGUCUCAGUUUCCAGAUGGAGCGACCCCUCGAGGAGCAAGUCCAGAGCAAGUGGUCGUCUAGUCAAGGCCGCACAGGAACAGGAGGGUCUGAUGUCCUCCAGAUGCAGAACAGUGAACACCAUGGACAAAGCAUCAAGACUCAAACUGACUCCAUCUCCCUUGAGGAUGUGGCUGUGAACUUCACCCUGGAGGAGUGGGCUUUGCUGGAUCCUGGCCAGAGGAAUAUCUACAGAGAUGUGAUGCGGGCAACCUUCAAGAACCUGGCCUGUAUAGGGGAAAAAUGGAAAGACCAGGAUAUUGAAGAUGAACACAAAAACCAGGGAAGAAAUCUAAGAAGUCCUAUGGUUGAAGCACUCUGUGAAAAUAAAGAAGAUUGUCCAUGUGGAAAAAGCACUAGCCAGAUUCCUGAUCUUAAUACGAACCUGGAAACUCCUACUGGAUUAAAACCAUGUGACUGCAGUGUGUGUGGGGAAGUCUUCAUGCAUCAGGUCUCCCUUAAUAGGCACAUGAGAUCUCACACUGAACAGAAACCAAAUGAGUGUCACGAAUAUGGAGAGAAGCCACAUAAAUGCAAAGAAUGUGGGAAAACCUUCACUCGCAGCUCCAGUAUUCGAACCCAUGAAAGAAUUCACACUGGAGAGAAACCCUAUGAAUGUAAGGAAUGUGGCAAAGCCUUCGCAUUUCUCUUUUCCUUUCGAAACCAUAUAAGAAUUCAUACUGGAGAGACACCCUAUGAAUGUAAGGAAUGUGGGAAGGCAUUCAGAUAUCUCACUGCUCUUCGGCGCCAUGAAAAAAAUCACACUGGAGAGAAACCCUACAAAUGUAAACAGUGUGGAAAAGCCUUUAUAUAUUACCAGCCUUUUCUAACCCACGAAAGGACUCACACUGGAGAGAAACCUUAUGAAUGUAAGCAAUGUGGGAAAGCCUUCAGUUGUCCCACGUACUUACGGAGUCAUGAGAAAACUCAUACUGGAGAGAAACCUUUUGUAUGUAGGGAAUGUGGGAGAGCCUUCUUUUCUCACUCAAGCCUUCGAAAACACGUGAAAACCCACACCGGAGUUCAACCUUAUACAUGUAAGAAAUGUGGGGAAGCCUUCAAGUCAUCUAGUUCCUGUGAAGUGCACGAAAGAACUCAUUUUGGAGAAAAACCCUAUGAAUGUAAACAAUGUGGUAAAGCCUUCAAUUCUUCAAGUUACCUUCAGUUGCACGAAAGAGUUCACACUGGCGAGAAAACUUACGAAUGUAAAGAAUGUGGUAAAGCCUUUCUUUAUUCCACUCACUUUCGAAUCCAUGAAAGAACCCAUACUAGAGAGAAACCCUAUGAAUGCAAACAGUGUGGUCGGGUCUUCAUUUACUUCAGUCACCUUCGAAGGCACGAAAGAAGUCACACUGGAGUGAAACCAUGUGAGUGUAAGCAGUGUGGCAAAGCUUUCACUUGUUUAAAUUCCCUGAAAGUACACAAAAGAAUUCAUACUGGAGAAAGACCCUUUCAGUGUAGACAAUGUGGUAAAGCCUUCAGUUACUCAAAGUCUUUGCACGUGCACGAAAGGACUCAUAGUAGACAGAAGCCCUAAGAAAGUAAAGUGUGGUAAUGCUGUCAGUUGUAUUAGUUCCUUUUGGAUGUAUGAGAGUACUUACGCUGGAGAGAAAUUCAAGGAAUGUAAACGGUGUGAUUAAGCCUUCAGUUGUCCUAAUUCCCUUUGAAGACGUGACUCAUGCGGCAAUGAAAUAUUUAACAAAUGGGGGAGGAACUUGCACUCUCCUGCGGGAUUGCAGAUAUGUGAAUGGACUCCAUGGACAGAAAAGCUACGAAUGUAUGGAGUGUAGGAAAGCCUUCACUUCACGUAAUCUUUUAAAGACACCUGAGAAUAUAUACUGGAGAGAAACUAUAAAGAAAAUUCUAUAUCCAUCCCAUCUUUUGUGGGGUUUGUUUUUUGUUUUUGUUUUUGUUGAGAUGUAAUUUUGCUCUUGUUGCCCAGGCUGGAGUGCAGUGGUGCGAUCGCGGCUCACCGCAACCUCCGCCUCCCGGAUUCAAGCAAUUCUCCUGCCGCAGCCUCCCAAGAAGCUGGGAUUACAGGCAUGCGCCACCACGCCUGGCUAAUUUUGUAAUUUUAGUAGAGAUGGGGUUUCUCCAUGUUGGUCAGGCUGGUCUCAAACUCCUGACCUCAGGUGAUCUGCCUGCCUCGGCCUCCCAAAGUGCUGGGAUUACAGGUGUGAGCCACAGCACCCAACCUUUUUUUCCCCGCCGCACCCCAAGAUGGUGUCUCACUCUGUUGCCCCAGGCUGGAGUGCAGUGGUGUGAUCCUGGCUCACUGUAACCUCUGGGUUCAAGCAAUUCUUCUGCCUCAGCCUUCCAAGUAGCUGGGAUUACAAGUGCCCACCACCAUGCCCAGCUAAUUUUUAUAUUUUUAGUAGAGACAGUGUUUCACCAUGUUGACCAGGCUGAUCUUAAACUCUUGACCUCAAAUGAUCCACCCACCUUGGCCUCCCAAAUUGUUCGUUUUACUUUUUUUUUUUUUUUUUUUUGAGCUGGAGUCUUACUCUGUUGCCUAGGCUGGAGUGAAAGUGGCGCAACCUCUGCCUCCCAGGUCAAAGCAAUCCUGCCUCAGGCCCCCUAGUAGCUGGCAUUACAGGCACAUGCCACCACGCCCAACUAAUUUUUAUAUUUUUAGUAGAGACGGGGUUUCACCAUGUUGGCCAGGCUGGUCUUGAACUCCUGACCUCAGGUAAUCCACCUGCCUUGGCCUCCCAAAGUGCUGGGAUUACAGGCGUGAGCCACCACACCCGGCCCCCAGUUCUUUUUUUUUUUUUUUGAGACGGAGUCCUUGCCCAGGCUGGAGUGCAGUGGCGCGAUCUCAGCUCACUGCAAGCUCCGCCUCCUGGGUUCACGCCAUUCUCCUGCCUCAGCCUCCCGAGUAGCUGGGACUACAGGCGCCCGCCACCACGCCCGGCUCAUUUUUUGUAUUUUUAGUGGAGACGGGGUUUCACCGUGUUAGCCAGGAUAGUCUUGAUCUCCUGACCUCGUGAUCCGCCCUCCUCGGCCUCCCAAAGUGCUGGGAUUAUAGGCGUGAGCCACCGCGCCCGGCCUCCAGUUCAUUUUAAAACCAUGAAACCACCCACACUGGAGAGCCACCUUCUUAAAUGUAAGCAAUAUGGGAACAUCUUCAAUGACAUCUGCAACCAUUGUCGAGAUUCUUCGUAGGAAGAAUUAAAGGAAUGGGGAAGAAGGACUUGGGCCCCAGCAGGCCUUUUGUGGCAUCCAGUCAGAAGUUAGGAAACACCCUCUAGGGCAGUGCCUGCCCUCAGCUCUCACACAUGACUGGAGAGAAGUGAGAAGACUCCCAGAAUCUGCCUUUUAAGUUUCCAUCAGUGUCCUCGGGUCAGACUGUGGGAAUGCUGUACUUCUAAGACAAAGGUUCGCAUCUUACAGUUUUUCCCCAAGUGGGAUCUGCCUAUGCACAUCCUAAUUCACAGACAUUGUCAGCAUUGCAUUAUUCCAGGGCUGUUUUGAGGUCAUCUCCAGCUCCAUUUCCCAUCUCAAACCUACACUUUGGACACUUGUUUAAACAUUCACAUCUGAAUUUCUCUGUGGCAACCGCAGGUGGCUCUGAGGUGAGAGACUGAAGAAGCAGAGCCUGUAUCAUGGGACACACACCCCUUGACCACACAGCAUCCACUCUCCUGCGGUUACCAGCCCUGCACCAACCACCACAGUCAGAAUAAUCUCAAAACUGCUAGUGGAGUCACAGACACACUCUGCCAUGUCUUAGCUGUAGGACACUCAGAAUUCUUACCUCCCCUAACUUGCUUUCCCUGUUUUCUGGCACAUUCUACCCUGAGAUAUUCAGCGGCAUAUGCACUGAUGAUGCUCCGGCCUUCUCACGUCAGUGCAUGUCACAUGCAUCCUGCUCCAGGACUGGUUUCCUAGCCUCCCGCUAAGACUAGCACUUAGCUCUUCUUGGAAAAGGACCCACCCUGCAGCGCUCCAGCUCUGUUGUGUAUGGGAGGUGCUGGUGUCAGGGUUCACAAGCCAUGGAACUACCUUGCUUCACAUCACAAGGCAAGGUGAACUCAACUCCCAAUAAACUGCUUGCUGGAGCCUCCGAAUUCUCCGUUUUCUGAAUUGCAUAGGCACGAUAGGGGUCGGGUCUGUCCUUUGUUGGAGUCAGUCCCCCCUUUUCUUAGCAAGUCAGUGUGUUUUAGAAGGGAGGUGGCAGCAUUGAGGGAAACCAGGUCACCAUCCACCCUCGUAACAACAGUCUCCCUGGGUGGGUCCCAGAAGUGAUCUUUGUGUCGCUCGGGUCGGAACUCUUUAGGCCUCUGGCCUCCACCCUCCCCCAACAGCAGGGAUGGGUCAGGUGGCAGCAUCCAAAACCACGGUGAAGAUACUAGGGUCCAGAGGCCGACUGGAGCAAGGUUUGCUGGCAGAUGAGGCCUCAGUGGAAGUGACGGCUACUGUGGAGAUGCAGUGGAGGACCUGGUGGCUGAGCCAGGAGAUGCACACCUUCGCUUCUCUCACCAGGAACAUUCGCUUCUCUCACCAGGAACAUUUAUGGUAGUAUGAGGGGUUGGAACAUUAUUACUCAACCCAUUUCAGGUCCUUUCACAUUCUUGAGCUGCCAUGUUGUGCUUUUGUAGAGAGAUGAUUAUUGUACUGUGGGAGGUCAGGAAGUUCGAGAUUCCUUCACUGUCAGAAUGGGCUCAAGGAGCCAUCUUUUGUGAUAGGUAUUGGGGAACUAAGGGGUAUCUCUGCUACAGGAAUGGGAGUGAGAACAUUCACUUUUUGAAGGACAAGUAUAUGUGGGUCUAUGAUGAUGUUUUUGUAAAACCCUUUUGUGUAUGUGUCUGUGUGAGUCCUAAUAUUCAGUAAGUAUUUUCCUCUGUGUAACUCCCUCUAAUAGGUGUAGUCAACAAAGCUGUGCUAAUAUCUCUGUCCCCUUGAUCCUGGCAUUCUGGAAGACACGAAAGCAAGCAAGGAUAUAUAAGGCACUGUGGUGGUUAUUCCCGAGGAGCCAGAGAAACCUGGAGAAGAGAUCAGAACACCUGGGGUCCUUCUAUUUGGGAGAAUCUUUUAGUAUCUGGGCUGUUACACCUGUGGGUUUGUGAAUUUGUGUCUGUCCACCUGUAUGUACAGUGAUAACGUGUGUGAUUUUUGUAUAUUUGUCUAGAGGGCUGUGUGUAUAUAUAUUUAUAUAUAUUUUUAAAUAUGGAAUGCUUUUAGGUUUUUUUUUUUUUUUUUUUUUUUGAGAUGGAUUCUCACUGUUGCCAGGCUGGAGUGCAGUGGCACAAUCUUGGCUCACUGCAACCUCCACUUCUCAGGUUCAAGCAAUUCUCCUGCCUCAGCCUCCUGAGUAGCUGGGACUAUAGGCGCGUGCCACCACAACCAGCUAAAUUUUUUUGUAUUUUUAGUAGAGAUGGGGUUUCACCAUGUUGACCAGGAUGGUCUCAAUCUCCUGACCUUGUGAUCCACCCACCUCGGUCUCCCCAAAGUGCUGGGAUUACAGGCGUGAGCCACUCUGCCUGGCUGGUUAUUUUGUUUGUUUGUUGUUUUUUUGAGACACAGUCUCGCUCUGUCACCAAGCUGGACUGCAGUGGCAUGAUCUCGGCUCACUGCAAUCUCUGCCUCCCAGGUUCAAGCAAUUCUCCUGUUUCAGCCUCCUGAGUAGCUGGGAUUACAGGCGCGUGCCACCAUACCGAGCUAGUUUUUUUAUUUUUAGUAGAGACGGGGUUUCACCAUGUUGGCCAGGAUGGUCUCGCCCUCCUGACCUUGUGAUCUGCCUGCCUCGGCCUCUCAAAGUGCUGGGAUUAGAGGCUUGAGCCACCAGGCCCGGCUGGAAUGCUUGCAUUUUCUUGCCUGAUUUCCCUGGGAGCACCCCCCUUAACACUGAAUGGAGCUGGUGAGAGCAAAUAUCCUUGUUUCUGAUAUUAGAUAUUAAAAAUAUGGUUUUUCACCAUCAAA